AGACCGCUGGAACAGCUGAGCAGAGCAGGUGGACUGCUGAGAUAGACCAGGGACACCAGGCAGCCACAGGCCUGUCAGACCAGGACCCUUACCCUCUAGACAUGGCCUCGGUCCCCUGCAAACCCCAGCCCCGUAGCCCUGCGAGGUUACAGACAGCCUAAACGCCACCACCACAGGGCCUGUGCCGUGCCCCUGACCCGGGCACAGAAGGCCACUGGCCCGGAGGCCAUGGAGACGGUGCCCCCAGCAGUGGACCUGGUGCUGGGUGCUUCUGCCUGCUGCCUGGCCUGUGUCUUCACCAACCCCCUGGAGGUGGUGAAGACGCGGCUGCAGCUGCAGGGGGAGCUGCAGGCCCGGGGCACCUACCCACGGCCCUACCAUGGCUUCAUAGCCUCUGUCGCUGCUGUGGCCCGAGCAGACGGGCUGUGGGGCCUGCAGAAGGGGCUGGCUGCCGGCCUUCUGUACCAAGGCCUCAUGAAUGGCGUUCGUUUCUACUGCUACAGCCUGGCGUGCCAGGCUGGCCUCACGCAGCAACCAGGUGGCACCGUGGUUGCGGGAGCCGUGGCGGGGGCACUGGGAGCCUUCGUGGGGAGCCCUGCUUACCUGAUCAAAACGCAGCUGCAAGCUCAGACAGUGGCCGCAGUGGCCGUGGGACACCAGCACAAUCACCAGACUGUCCUGGGUGCCUUGGAGACCAUCUGGCGGCAGCAAGGGCUCUUGGGGCUGUGGCAGGGCGUUGGUGGGGCUGUGCCCCGAGUCAUGGUGGGCUCAGCUGCCCAGCUGGCCACCUUCGCCUCUGCCAAGGCCUGGGUACAGAAGCAACAGUGGCUCCCUGAGGACAGCUGGCUGGUGGCCCUGGCUGGGGGCAUGAUCAGCAGCAUAGCCGUGGUUGUCGUCAUGACUCCCUUCGAUGUGGUCAGCACGCGGCUAUACAAUCAGCCGGUGGACACAGCUGGCAGGGGCCAGCUCUAUGGGGGCCUCACCGACUGCAUGGUGAAGAUCUGGCGGCAGGAGGGCCCCCUGGCACUCUACAAGGGCCUGGGCCCCGCCUACCUGCGCCUGGGCCCCCACACCAUCCUCAGCAUGCUCUUCUGGGACGAGCUUCGGAAACUGGCUGGGCGGGCCCAGCACAAGGGCACCUAGACGACGGCCCUCACCCCCACGUCCUGACACGGCCGGCACUUGGCCGGAAGUGAGAGCCUGCUCCAGGACAACUGGCUGUCCCGGGGCGGGCCAUGGGCCCAGGCCCUGCCAGAGGUCCCGGGAGAGUGUGGACAGCUCUGGUCCAUCCAGCCCCUUGGCCCACCCAGGUCCAGAGCAUCCACUUCAAGUUACCACCCAUUCUGUCUUCCAGACAGUUCUCUUCCUUCUCUGUACUGCGUACUGGGUCACCACAUCCCAGAGCCUUGCUCAGUUAUAGCAACUGCUGCGGGCGUGCACAUGGCAUAGGCCCAGUAACUUACAUACAUCGGCUCACUUAGGCCUCAGACAGCAGCACGAGGCAGGCACUUUUACUUCUUUUACCAUUAGAAAGCCAAGGCCUAGAGUGGUGGGCUUUGACCACAGCCACACAAUUUUGAAGUGGCAGAGCCAGGACUGGAGCUUAGCCCUGCUCACCCUAGACCUAUGCGCUUGACAAGUGCGUGACUGUGACAGGCCCAUGGGCCCGGACUGCCCAUAGGGGUCACUGUACCAUGGCAAAGGCUGAGGUGCACCAGGAGGCUGUGGCGUCGUCACCUGCCUUAUUUGCUGGAGAAGCUGUAGCAAAGAACCACAGACUGGGCGACUUAGACAAUAGAAAUGUAUUUUCUCACAGUUCUGGAGGCUGGAUGCUGGAGACCAAGGUGUCAGUGGGCUGGUUUCUUCUGAGGCCUCUGUCCAUGGCUUGCAGAUGCUGCUUUCUCUCUGUGUCUGCACAUGGUGGUCCCUCGAUGUGCGUCUGGGUCCUGAUCUCCUCCUCUUAUAAGGACACAAAUCAUGUUGGCUUAGGGCCCACCCUCAUGACCCCACUUUAAUUUUUUUUUUUUUUUUUGAGAUGAAGUCUCACUCUGCCACCCAAGCUGGAGUGCAGUGGCACGAUCUCGGUUCACUGCAACCUUGGCCUCCUAGGUUCAAGCAAUUCUCCUGCCCCAGCCUCCUGAGUAGCUGGGAUUACAGGUGUGUGCCACCACACCCGGCCAAUUUUUGUAUCUUUAGUAGAGAUGGGGUUUUGCCAUGUUGGCCAGACUGGUCUCGAACUCCUGACCUCAAGUGAUCCACUGGCCUUGGCCUCCCAAAGUGCUGGGAUUACAGGCAUGAGCCACCUCACUUGGCCCAAUUUUAACUUAAUUAUCUCUGUCAAGAGCCUAUCUCCAUAUACAGUCACAUCCUGAGCUACUAGGGGGUAGGACUUCAACAUGCACUUCUGCAGGGGCCGCAGUUCAGCCAACAUCAUCUUUUUUUUUGAGAUGGAGUCUCGCUUUGUUGCCCAGGCUGGAGUGCGGUGGUGCAAUCUCGGCUCACCACAACCUCCACCUCCCAGGUUCAAGUGAUUCUCCUGCCUCAGCCUCCCGAGUUGCUGGGACUAUAGGUGUGCGCCACCAUGCCCAGCUAAUUUUGUAUUUUUAGUAGAGACAGGCUUUCGCUGUGUUGGCCAGGCUGGUCUUGAAUGCCUGACCUUGCCGCCCGCCUCGGCCUCCCAAAAUGCUGGGAUUACAGGCGUGAGCCACCGCGCCUGGCCUCAGCCAACAUCAUCUAAGGGCUCUCACGGAGGGCCUCCCAGCUGCCCGCCCUGUGGGCAUUUGCACAUAUCCUGACAAGCCUGAAAGAAGCUCCGGGUGCCCAUUGUUCAGUCCAGGUGCCCAUUGUUCCCGGGACUGAGGCCCGGGAAAGGGAAGCGACGUGGCAGGGCCAGCAGCAGACCCUGGGCCUUUCUCUAGACUGAGCACCAUUCCCCGUGGGUGUGCUCUCAGCGCCGCACCGACCUUCACACUGCAGAGAUGGAUGCCAACUCCCUGGCAGGGGCAGGACUGCUGCCGAGCAGCCCCACCUGCCCUCCCAGCCACACCCCAAGUCUGUAAGGGCCGCUCCCAGGAACACCUGCUACUGCACACUCCAAACCAAUAAAGUUUUAUAUUUUGUUUACUUCAA